UUAUGUUUAUUGUCCUGUUCAAAUCCAAGCUCUUUCACACAGAAUUGUACAAGCAAAGUUUGAGUAACUAAUCUUGGGGUCAUAUUCCAAUGUGGCUCCCAUUAAAGCAUUUCAAAGAGUGCUAGAUUCAGGCUCACAUAUGUUACAGCAACAGGCUAUACUCUAGGGAAAGAACAAAACAGCUUGAUAAAAACUGUUUCCUUUUAAGCAUAUUUAGACAAAUAUCUAUCCUGUAUUCUCUUUGCCAUCUAGAUUGGAGCCAUGGCUUUGGAACAGAACCAGUCAACAGAUUAUUAUUAUGAGGAAAAUGAAAUGAAUGGCACUUAUGACUACAGUCAAUAUGAACUGAUCUGUAUCAAAGAAGAUGUCAGAGAAUUUGCAAAAGUUUUCCUCCCUGUAUUCCUCACAAUAGUUUUCGUCAUUGGACUUGCAGGCAAUUCCAUGGUAGUGGCAAUUUAUGCCUAUUACAAGAAACAGAGAACCAAAACAGAUGUGUACAUCCUGAAUUUGGCUGUAGCAGAUUUACUCCUUCUAUUCACUCUGCCUUUUUGGGCUGUUAAUGCAGUUCAUGGGUGGGUUUUAGGGAAAAUAAUGUGCAAAAUAACUUCAGCCUUGUACACACUAAACUUUGUCUCUGGAAUGCAGUUUCUGGCUUGUAUCAGCAUAGACAGAUAUGUGGCAGUAACUAAAGUCCCCAGCCAAUCAGGAGUGGGAAAACCAUGCUGGAUCAUCUGUUUCUGUGUCUGGAUGGCUGCCAUCUUGCUGAGCAUACCCCAGCUGGUUUUUUAUACAGUAAAUGACAAUGCUAGGUGCAUUCCCAUUUUCCCCCGCUACCUAGGAACAUCAAUGAAAGCAUUGAUUCAAAUGCUAGAGAUCUGCAUUGGAUUUGUAGUACCCUUUCUUAUUAUGGGGGUGUGCUACUUUAUCACAGCAAGGACACUCAUGAAGAUGCCAAACAUUAAAAUAUCUCGACCCCUAAAAGUUCUGCUCACAGUCGUUAUAGUUUUCAUUGUCACUCAACUGCCUUAUAACAUUGUCAAGUUCUGCCGAGCCAUAGACAUCAUCUACUCCCUGAUCACCAGCUGCAACAUGAGCAAACGCAUGGACAUCGCCAUCCAAGUCACAGAAAGCAUCGCACUCUUUCACAGCUGCCUCAACCCAAUCCUUUAUGUUUUUAUGGGAGCAUCUUUCAAAAACUACGUUAUGAAAGUGGCCAAGAAAUAUGGGUCCUGGAGAAGACAGAGACAAAGUGUGGAGGAGUUUCCUUUUGAUUCUGAGGGUCCUACAGAGCCAACCAGUACUUUUAGCAUUUAAAGGUAAAACUGCUCUGCCUUUUGCUUGGAUACAUAUGAAUGAUGCUUUCCCCUCAAAUAAAACAUCUGCAUUAUUCUGAAACUCAAAUCUCAGACGCCGUGGUUGCAACUUAUAAUAAAGAAUGGGUUGGGGGAAGGGGGAGAAAUAAAAGCCAAGAAGAGGAAACAAGAUAAUAAAUGUACAAAACAUGAAAAUUAAAAUGAACAAUAUAGGAAAAUAAUUGUAACAGGCAUAAGUGAAUAACACUCUGCUGUAACGAAGAAGAGCUUUGUGGUGAUAAUUUUGUAUCUUGGUUGCAGUGGUGCUUAUACAAAUCUACACAAGUGAUAAAAUGACACAGAACUAUAUACACACAUUGUACCAAUUUCAAUUUCCUGGUUUUGACAUUAUAGUAUAAUUAUGUAAGAUGGAACCAUUGGGGAAAACUGGGUGAAGGGUACCCAGGACCACUCUGUACCAUCUUUGUAACUUCCUGUGAAUUUAUAAUAAUUUCAAAAUAAAACAAGUUAAAAAAAAACCCACUAUGCUAUAAGUUAGGCCAUCUAAAACAGAUUAUUAAAGAGGUUCAUGUUAAAAGGCAUUUAUAAUUAUUUUUAAUUAUCUAAGUUUUAAUACAAGAACGAUUUCCCUGCAUAAUUUUAGUACUUGAAUAAGUAUGCAGCAGAACUCCAACUAUCUUUUUUCCUGUUUUUUUUAAAUUUGUAAGUAAUUUUAUAAAAUCCACCUCCUCCAAAAAAGCAAUAAAAAAAAAACAAACUAUAAUAAGCUUUUCUGAUUCUUUUCAAAACAUUCCUGGUAAGUUCCUAAAGACAUAAUUUGCUUCUAUGAUGUCAACUUUCUUACUAAUAACUGGUUAUCAUGACAAAUGUUAGGUUUAUCAUAUAUAGUCUAGGUGUAAUCCUCAGACUAUCAUUUUCAUCUGGGUUCCAAUUUCUUAACUUCCUAAAGAAUUCAUCUGUUUAUACAAGUCUACCACUGCCGAUUGACUAAAAAAUACAUUAUCCCAUGCAUAAAAUGUCCUAUUUUCAUUUAAACACUUUAUUUUUGAGUAAUAAAAAUAUGUACCACAAUAAAUUAUUGUUAAUUAACAUGUACAGCUUAUCUUUUUUAAAAAAAUUUGCUGUAAAUUAUUAUAAUCCAUGUAAUAUGCUCCUACUAAAAUUAAAUUUUGCUAGCAAUUACAUUGGUCAAAAA